CUCUUGUUUUGGUCUCGCGGGCUAGUAGGGCGCACUUGGCGGGGAGGCGCUUGGGCGCGAGACUAGGCGUGAAGAGCAGAGCUGCGCGCGCACUCGGGAAAGGGGGGAAGGGAGCAGGGUCCAGGCAGGGGGGGUUAGGCCCCCUGAUCCCCCUCGUUACCCCGACUGGCACGGAAUAAGGGGAGGAAAUGAUCGAGAUGGCGGCGGAGAAGGAGCCGUUUCUGGUGCCGGCCCCGCCGCCGCCGCUCAAAGAUGAGUCGGGCGGAGGGGGCGGCCCCACGGUGCCACCGCACCAAGAGGCCGCCUCUGGGGAGCUCCGCGGCGGGACGGAGCGUGGUCCGGGUCGUUGCGCGCCAUCUGCGGGGUCCCCAGCCGCUGCGGUCGGUCGGGAAAGCCCCGGGGCCGCGGCCACCUCCUCCAGUGGUCCCCAGGCGCAGCAGCACCGAGGGGGCGGCCCCCAGGCGCAGUCGCAUGGGGAGGCCCGCCUGUCGGAUCCCCCGGGGCGAGCCGCUCCCCCGGACGUGGGGGAGGAGCGCCGGGGAGGGGGCGGGACAGAGCUGGGUCCCCCUGCUCCUCCUCGACCCCGCAAUGGCUAUCAGCCCCACCGGCCACCUGGGGGGGGCGGGGGCAAGAGGAGAAAUAGCUGUAAUGUAGGGGGAGGCGGGGGAGGCUUCAAACAUCCGGCCUUCAAGAGGCGCAGGCGGGUGAAUUCGGACUGUGACUCUGUGUUACCCUCCAACUUCCUCCUGGGGGGCAAUAUCUUUGAUCCCCUGAACCUGAAUAGCCUCCUGGAUGAGGAAGUGAGCCGCACUCUCAACGCGGAGACCCCUAAGUCAUCCCCCCUUCCGGCCAAAGGGCGAGAUCCGGUGGAGAUCCUCAUCCCCAAAGAUAUUACUGACCCGCUCAGUCUCAAUACUUGCACUGAUGAGGGCCAUGUAGUUCUUGCUUCGCCACUCAAGACUGGUCGGAAGCGGCAUAGACACCGGGGACAGCACCACCAGCAGCAGCAGGCAGCCGGAGGGAGUGAGAGUCACCCCGUGCCGCCCACAGCCCCUCUCACCCCCUUACUCCACGGGGAGGGCGCCUCACAGCAGCCGCGGCACAGGGGCCAGAACCGGGAUGCCCCCCAACCCUAUGAACUCAACACAGCCAUCAACUGCAGGGAUGAAGUGGUGUCUCCCCUUCCAUCUGCUCUGCAGGGUCCCUCAGGCUCCCUAUCAGCCCCUCCAGCUGCCUCAGUUAUCUCUGCACCCCCAUCUUCCUCCUCCCGACAUCGCAAACGUCGCAGGACUUCCAGCAAGUCGGAGGCAGGGGCUAGGGGUGGAGGCCAGGGUUCCAAGGAAAAGGGCCGAGGGAGUUGGGGAGGCCGCCACCACCACCACCACCCACUGCCUGCAGCAGGCUUCAAAAAGCAACAGCGCAAGUUCCAGUAUGGGAAUUAUUGCAAAUACUAUGGGUACCGCAAUCCUUCCUGUGAGGAUGGGCGCCUUCGGGUGUUGAAGCCUGAGUGGUUUCGGGGCCGGGACGUCCUAGAUCUGGGCUGCAAUGUGGGCCAUCUGACCCUGAGCAUUGCCUGCAAGUGGGGCCCGUCCCGCAUGGUGGGCCUGGAUAUCGAUUCCCGGCUCAUCCAUUCUGCCCGCCAAAACAUCCGACACUACCUUUCCGAGGAGCUGCGUCUCCCACCCCAGACUUUGGAAGGGGACCCGGGGGCAGAGGGUGAGGAAGGGACCACCACCGUUCGAAAGAGGAGCUGCUUCCCAGCCUCGCUGACUGCCAGCCGGGGUCCCAUCGCUGCCCCCCAAGUGCCCUUGGAUGGAGCGGACACAUCAGUCUUCCCCAACAAUGUUGUCUUCGUCACGGGUAAUUAUGUGCUGGAUCGAGAUGACCUGGUGGAGGCCCAAACACCUGAGUAUGAUGUGGUGCUCUGCCUCAGCCUCACCAAGUGGGUGCAUCUGAACUGGGGAGACGAGGGCCUGAAGCGCAUGUUUCGCCGGAUCUACCGGCACCUACGCCCUGGGGGCAUCCUGGUCCUAGAGCCCCAACCCUGGUCGUCGUAUGGCAAGAGAAAGACUCUUACAGAAACGAUCUACAAGAACUACUACCGAAUCCAAUUGAAGCCAGAGCAGUUCAGUUCCUACCUGACAUCCCCAGACGUGGGCUUCUCCAGCUAUGAGCUUGUGGCCACACCCCACAACACCUCUAAAGGCUUCCAGCGUCCUGUGUACCUGUUCCACAAGGCCCGAUCCCCCAGCCACUAAGUGGCCCCCUAAACAGAAAGUGUGAAGAGGCUGCCCUCGCUGCUCAUAAGGACCUGGGGGAAGAGGAAAGUGUCCCAAGGUCUUUCCUUUCUGACUCCAAAAAUAGUUUCCUUUCUUGGAUCUGCAAAGAAAGCUUUUCUUCCGUCGCUGCCUCAGCCUCCUCCCUAUGCCUCUGGCACCUGCGCAGCAAGGCUGGCUGUGCUGGAGUCACCAUCAUCUUCCUCUCCCCCAGCCUCCCAGGCUGGAUGGCAUGGACUGUUUGCUGACCUCUGUUCUCUUAGGGCAUGGGAGGUGGGAGGAUAUCAAAUUCUCUAGCCCUUUCCUCCUAUUCUCCCAAGGAGAGAGAUUCCCAUUUCUCCUCGGCCAUUGUACCUAGCUCUUGUCCCUAGCUGCAUUUCAGUGGACCAUGGAUAGAGGGACUGAGGGUUAGACGGGGAAGACUGGCAGGGAGGCACGCAGGUACUGUGAAAAUCCUUCCCUUUGCCCUCCCCCAGUGGGAGAGGGGGUUGGGUUUUCAAUGUGAGAACAGCACAAUAAACUUGAUGUCUAGGGCAGUGGCCCCCA